ACUCCGCAGCCCGUUCAGGACCCCGGCGCGGGCAGGGCGCCCACGAGCUGGCUGGCUGCUUGCACCCACAUCCUUCUUUCUCUGGGACCUGGGGUCGCGGUUACUUGGGCUGGCCGGCGAACCCUUGAGUGGCCUGGCGGGGAGCGGGCCUCGCGCGCCUGGAGGGCCCUGUGGAACGAAGAGAGGCACACAGCAUGGCAGAAAACCGAGAGCCCCGCGGUGCUGUGGAGGCUGAACUGGAUCCAGUGGAAUACACCCUUAGGAAAAGGCUUCCCAGCCGCCUGCCCCGGAGACCCAAUGACAUUUAUGUCAACAUGAAGACGGACUUUAAGGCCCAGCUGGCCCGCUGCCAGAAGCUGCUGGACGGAGGGGCCCGGGGUCAGAACGCGUGCUCUGAGAUCUACAUUCACGGCUUGGGCCUGGCCAUCAACCGCGCCAUCAACAUCGCGCUGCAGCUGCAGGCGGGCAGCUUCGGGUCCUUGCAGGUGGCUGCCAAUACCUCCACCGUGGAGCUUGUUGAUGAGCUGGAGCCAGAGACCGACACACGGGAGCCACUGACUCGGAUCCGCAACAACUCAGCCAUCCACAUCCGAGUCUUCAGGGUCACACCCAAGUAAUUGAAAAGACACUCCUCCACUUAUCCCCUCCGUGAUAUGGCUCUUCGCAUGCUGAGUACUGGACCUCGGACCAGAGCCAUGUAAGAAAAGGCCUGUUCCCUGGAAGCCCAAAGGACUCUGCAUUGAGGGUGGGGGUAAUUGUCUCUUGGUGGGCCCAGUUAGUGGGCCUUCCUGAGUGUGUGUAUGCGGUCUGUAACUAUUGCCAUAUAAAUAAAAAAUCCUGUUGCACUAGU